AGCGGAGCCGGCGCCGCCGCCAUGUUGGGUCUGAAGCGGCUGCUGUAGGCGCCGACGGAGCGAGCGGGCGUGCGGAGCGGGCGACAGUGGCGUGGGAUCUGCCUCUCUGCGAGCAGCUGGGAGCGGCGGCGGCGGCGCCAUGAGCGGGGGCACCCCUUACAUCGGCAGCAAGAUCAGCCUCAUCUCCAAGGCGGAGAUCCGCUACGAGGGCAUCCUCUACACCAUCGACACCGAAAACUCCACCGUAGCCCUUGCCAAAGGUACGCGGGACCGGGCCUCAGGGUGGGGGCCGAGCCGGGCGCCGCUCGGGGCUGCUCCCCGCUCCGGCCCGCGGCCUCCUCGUUCCCUCCCCUCCCUCCGUCGAGCUCCGGGAGGCCUCUCGCCUCCCUUCUCCGGGCCCCGGCGUCGCGGGCCGGACCGCGGCCUCCCCGCGGCUCCCUGGUUUCCGCCCCCCGGAAUGUCCGCGCCUGAAGCCCGGGGAACUACGGGACUGAGUGCGCGGCGGGCGGCCCUGAAGUCCGAGAACGGGCCGGAGAACACGGAGAAACGCGUCUUCCAACUCCGAAAUUCGGGGCUUCUGCCGUCUUAGCACAAAACAAAGCCGGAGUAUUCAAAGAAUUUUUCCGCCCAGCUUGAGUUCAUCGCGGAUGCGUUGACUACACAGCACCCAUUUUCUCACUUUGUUCAUUUCAAUUCGUGGCGAUCUUCCUCUGGUGAACUCUUGAGUAAUGUGCUAAAACUUUGGGUUUGCUCUGCGACGCAGACAUUCUCGAAAUGCCAUCGAUGCCGUGGAGCAGAUCCCAUCUCCCUCGGCUCAUCCUCUGUUGGUAUUUACCUGUUAAACCGGAAUCCUCAAAGCCUGUUGUGCAACCACCUCAUUAGGGCGCGUGGUAAAAAUGCUUGCUGCUGCCCCGACGCCCCUGUUUCUGGAAACGGGUUCAAGCUUGAUCCAGGAUCCUUCUUGACCAGUUCGAUCCUUUGGUACAGAAGACAGACCGACAGAUCGUCCAAUACCACCUCGAGAUGAAGUCUUUGAAUACAUUAUAUUCCGUGGGAGUGACAUUAAAGACCUUACUGUUUGUGAGCCACCAAAACCACAGUGUUCUUUGCCUCAAGACCCAGCUAUUGUUCAGUCCUCACUAGGCUCAUCGACUUCUUCAUUCCAGUCCAUGGGUUCUUAUGGACCUUUCGGCAGGAUGCCCACAUACAGUCAGUUCAGUCCGAGUUCCUUAGUUGGGCAGCAGUUUGGUGCUGUUGGUGUUGCUGGAAGCUCUUUGACAUCCUUUGGAACAGAAACAUCAAACAGUGGUACCUUACCCCAAAGUAGUGCGGUUGGUUCUGCCUUUACACAGGAUACAAGAUCUCUAAAAACACAGUUAUCUCAAGGUCGCUCAAGCCCUCAGUUAGACCCUUUGAGAAAAAGCCCAACCAUGGAACAAGCAGUGCAGACCGCCUCAGCCCACUUACCUGCUCCAGCAGCUGUUGGGAGAAGGAGUCCUGUAUCAACCAGGCCUUUGCCAUCUGCCAGCCAAAAGGCAGGAGAGAAUCAGGAGCACAGGCGAGCUGAAGUACACAAAGUUUCAAGGCCAGAAAAUGAGCAACUCAGAAAUGAUAACAAGAGACAAGUAGCUCCAGGUGCUCCUUCAGCUCCAAGGAGAGGGCGUGGGGGUCAUCGGGGUGGCAGGGGAAGAUUUGGUAUUCGGCGAGAUGGGCCAAUGAAAUUUGAGAAAGACUUUGACUUUGAAAGUGCAAAUGCACAAUUCAACAAGGAAGAGAUUGACAGAGAGUUUCAUAAUAAACUUAAAUUAAAAGAAGAUAAACUUGAGAAACAGGAGAAGCCUGUAAAUGGUGAAGAUAAAGGAGACUCAGGAGUUGAUACCCAAAACAGUGAAGGAAAUGCCGAUGAAGAAGAUCCACUUGGACCUAAUUGCUAUUAUGACAAAACUAAAUCCUUCUUUGAUAAUAUUUCUUGUGAUGACAAUAGAGAACGGAGACCAACCUGGGCUGAAGAAAGAAGAUUAAAUGCUGAAACAUUUGGAAUCCCACUUCGUCCAAACCGUGGCCGUGGGGGAUACAGAGGCAGAGGAGGUCUUGGUUUCCGUGGUGGCAGAGGGCGUGGUGGUGGCAGAGGUGGUACCUUCACUGCCCCUCGAGGAUUUCGCGGUGGAUUCAGAGGAGGUCGUGGGGGCCGGGAGUUUGCGGAUUUUGAAUAUAGGAAAGACAACAAAGUUGCUGCAUAGUCUACAAACAAGUCUCUGAAAAUAGGUGAAUUUCUAGCUCUUCAUGGUCCUGAACAUUGAUUUCAGUCUUUGCAAAGAAUGAAGAAGUGAAUUCGCUGUACAUUUGUCACCAGCACUGGGUUUUUGUUUUUUGUUUGUUUUUCCGCUUAAUUUCAAAGAUAAAAUGCAGUUACUUUUGGGGGUGGAAGGCUCAUCUUAAAACAUGAGCAUUAAAUAUAUUUGGAAUAGCAGAAGGUUAAGUAAUUUCUUAUGUAUAGUUAAACUAAAGCAGUACUUCAGUGGGACUUAACAAGUAUUUUUUCAUCACUGAAAGGUUUUUUUUUUUUAUCACUAAAUUGUAUUUGGCAAUUGCAAGUUGCCUGCAGAUAGGGCCGUGAUACUGUGUUUUGAGCCACAGAAGGUUGUGUGUGUGUGUGUGUGUGUGUGUGUGUGUGUGUGUGUGUGUAUGUGUGUGUCUUUUUCCUCCUUUCUUUUGGGGAAUCCUGUAAUAUGAGGUAGCUUAUUUCGUCAAUUAAUUAGGGUGCUGGAUGGUAGAGAAUUUUGUCAGUCAACUAUGUACACACAGUAAAUACUGUUUCUUAGGCAAAGGUAACUUUUUUAUAUAGUUGUAAAAUUCCAUUAUAUUCCAUUGCCAAAGAAACAUUAAGAACUUUGUAUAGCUGUAUAAAAAGCAACUAAUUUUUUAAAGAAUAAACAUUUUAAAGUCAGCAAACAUACUGUGUCCUUGCAGAAGUUGAUGUGCUGAGCAGCAGCCUUAUGGGUGGGUCUUUUUUUCUUAGUUUUCCAGGCUUAACAUUUUUGAUUUUGUUUUUUAAUGUUUGGAACAUAAAUGAAGAUUUGAUACAUUAUUUCAUUAUCUAAAAAGGAUUAAUUAUUCAUGCUCAUUGUAAGAACUUCAUUUUGUAGCAAAUGGCAUAUCACAGGAUCUGUCCAGAUAAUCGAUAUUUUCAGUAUACAAAUGUAAAUAAUCACAGAUGAGAAUGUACUUAGCUGUAUUUUCAAAUAAGUAAUCUUCCCCCCUUUUGUAGGACUUUAAAACUAGGCAUCAAUGAACCUGUUUUUCCUAUUAUGCCUGGAAUUUAGUCAUGAUACCUUGACUCAUUCCAUCAUAUUUCAAGAGGAUUCAGAGUGCUAGAAAUUAUUUUGGUAGCCUGUAACACACGGCAACACUGGUCCUUGGGCCUAUGAUGACCCACAGAUGACUCAGUAUAGAGUUCAUUGCUAAUUAUAAAUUACUAGUGAAUCUUUUUGAUAUUUUAAGCUCUAGUGGGAAAAAUCUGGCCACUUUUGUGUUUUUAUGAAGGCCAUGGAAUAAAAGGAUCCAAAGAUUUAAAUAUUUUUAUCUAAUAUUUUGAUUGUUUUCUUAACUUUCUCCUUAAAACAUUCAGUAGUGAUAAAGAUAUAGAAACUGCACUGUAGGAGAAUUGGAAUAUUUAAGGCUGGUUGACAUUUUUUAUUUUCAUUUUAUAUCUUUUGUAUAGCUCUACAAGGCAGUGUUUUGUAAUUUGGUUUCAUUAUGAAGAUCCAGUACUUGGCAGCCAUAGUUUAGACAAUAUUGUUCAGUGCUGUUUGCUUGCAUGUUAACAACAAAACCUUUUAGAGGACCCACAAAUCAUGAUAUUGAACACAGUUCCGAGGCAUUCAGAGCAUCAGAGCAAGUACCAUGGCAAUACAUGUGUAGACUGUUGGAGAUGUCCCGGGCCAAUUUCAAGAAAGAAAACUGUAAAUACUAGUUCUACUUGCUCUGAAAUUAUGAGUUUAUGCGUUUUCCCAGCCCUCCGAAUCACUGACUGGGGCGUUUUGUGCCCCAGCAAUAACUGGCAGCAUGGCAUACCUGCAGUACCCCUUACAAUAUUAAAGCAAAGUUUUUAUUCUAAAACAGAAUAAAACUGUUCAAUAAAAAA